CACCGGCAGCACCAUGUCGCUCACGGUCGUCAGCAUGGCGUGUGUUGGGUUCUUCUUGCUGCAGGGGGCCUGGCCACAUGAGGGAGUCCACAGAAAACCUUCCCUCCUGGCCCACCCAGGUCGCCUGGUGAAAUCAGAAGAGACAGUCAUCCUGCAAUGUUGGUCAGAUGUCAUGUUUGAACACUUCCUUCUGCACAGAGAGGGGAUGUUUAACGACACUUUGCGCCUCAUUGGAGAACACCAUGAUGGGGUCUCCAAGGCCAACUUCUCCAUCAGUCGCAUGAAGCAAGACCUGGCAGGGACCUACAGAUGCUACGGUUCUGUUACUCACUCCCCCUAUCAGUUGUCAGCUCCCAGUGACCCUCUGGACAUCGUGAUCAUAGGUCUAUAUGAGAAACCUUCUCUCUCAGCCCAGCCGGGCCCCACGGUUCUGGCAGGAGAGAAUGUGACCUUGUCCUGCAGCUCCCGGAGCUCCUAUGACAUGUACCAUCUAUCCAGGGAAGGGGAGGCCCAUGAACGUAGGCUCCCUGCAGGGACCAAGGUCAACGGAACAUUCCAGGCCAACUUUCCUCUGGGCCCUGCCACCCAUGGAGGGACCUACAGAUGCUUCGGCUCUUUCCGUGACUCUCCAUACGAGUGGUCAAAGUCAAGUGACCCACUGCUUGUUUCUGUCACAGGAAACCCUUCAAAUAGUUGGCCUUCACCCACUGAACCAAGCUCCGAAACCGGUAACCCCAGACACCUACAUGUUCUGAUUGGGACCUCAGUGGUCAAAAUCCCUUUCACCAUCCUCCUCUUCUUUCUCCUUCAUCGCUGGUGCUCCGACAAAAAAAAUGCUGCUGUAAUGGACCAAGAGCCUGCAGGGAACAGAACAGUGAACAGCGAGGAUUCUGAUGAACAAGACCAUCAGGAGGUGUCAUACGCAUAAUUGGAUCACUGUGUUUUCACACAGAGAAAAAUCACUCGCCCUUCUGAGAGGCCCAAGACACCCCCAACAGAUACCAGCAUGUACAUAGAACUUCCAAAUGCUGAGCCCAGAUCCAAAGUUGUCUUCUGUCCACGAGCACCACAGUCAGGCCUUGAGGGGAUCUUCUAGGGAGA